ACUUCCGCAAGGACCCUUUGGAAGGCCGGGUGGGCCGAGGUGAGAGUCCCCCUGCCGAGCCGCGGGAUCCAGGGCCUGCUGUGCUGGGCGCAGCCGGCCGGGGGCUGCGGGCCCCGAGCCCCUUUCGACCCUGGGGCCGCGUCUCUGGAGCGAAGUUUCUCUCUGCAGCUUCUUCGGGGGCCCGCUCUGAGCUCAGGGCCUGGCACUGGCUCCAAGGUACCUAGAGUCAUACAGGCAGAGAGUUGGCCAGAAGUUAGUUAUAUUUGGAUUUCUCAUCCUGCAUUUUCUCAACCCCUCACUCCCAUCCAAGCUGGGAGAGAAAUGACGAAGGCGGCCUUUUGCUACCUCCAGGCCUCGCGGGUUGUAGGUCAUGGGUGCCCCUGCUUCUCCUGUCGAGACAGUUCUUGGGAGAUUCUCGUCGACCCAGGAAUCGGCCGCUUUCCUUGCCCCUUCUGCAGGAGCGGGGCUUGAUUCUUAGCCAGAAUAGGAAGGAAUCUUCGAAGAGAAUGGGCCAGGAAAGUUUGAUUGUAGCCUCCUCCCCCGCCCUCUUUUCGAGCGAAGAAUAUGUGUGCUUAAAAGUAGAAUCGGCAGGCCGCCCCCAGAGGGUGGUUCUAUCGAAGCCAUCCUGCACGUGAGGCUGGUGGCUGUGUGUGAACUGGGUCAACCAGUGUAAGAAUCCGAAUGGUCUAUCAGAGAAUGCUUACAACCUCCCCUAGGUGAUCCUGAGAGUUCUAAUUCCAGCUUAGGGGGAAAAUGAUUGUGACUUAACUUGCUGGGCAACAGUGGUUUUUAACGGAGCUGCUCCCUUCCCAAAGUUAGUGUGUGUCAGAAUUGCCAGGGCAGCUGGUUAAAAAUGCAGAUUCCUAGUCCCCACUCGAAAUUGAUUAUAGUAGAUUGAGCUUUUUUGCUGGGAUCCAGGUUUCUGCACCAGGGGCUUGUGAUGUAGGUUGCCCCGAGACCACCGUUUUGGAAGAUCAGCUUUAUAAUCUUUGUUUCUUCUGUUGGAGGGAUUGGAAAACAGGUUUCAGAAGGAAGUUCUUUGCUAGGAGAUUGAUACUGUAUGCUGGGUUCAGAGGCUACCAAAUUGGCAGUAUGCCACCUCCAGACAACCAGGAGACAGACUCACUCUUCACUUUCUCUCAUUCUUUUUCUGCGAUGCCCAGAUUUGGCUCUUGCUUUUACUAAAAUAGUUAGUUCUUCCCAAGUCGAUUGCAGUGUCCUGGAGUUUGUUAUAUUAAGGAGUUUAUUGCCUUUCACACAUGUGAGGGUCUUGGGACACAGGGCUGUUUUGUGAAGUUCUAUGUUUGUCUUGGAGUUUGUUGAGCCCUGGCAUGUAGAUCACAGUAGCCUGGGUUCAGCUGACUCAGGGCUCCAGUCUUUAGCAGCGGUAACAGCAGCCAAAGCCAGACUUUAUAGCAGGAGGUCAUUACUAUCUCUAUCCUGGACCCUUCCUCUUUCUUCACGAGUGUGGGCAGGGAGGAAAGAGCCCUUGAGGAAACUAGACAGUUUGUGGACUUUGCCUCUUGAGAUAGCGGUGGUGAGGGUGCUGAGCGGAUGGUUUCUUUCACUUAGCAGAUACCAGGCCUUACAUUGGUUACAUCGUCCUAUUCAGUCUGUUGUGCAGAGAAUAAAGCCGAGUAAGACCACACAGGUUUAGUUCCCAGAUACUGCCCUUAUUCAGAAAUUCUGGUUUUAAUUUGCUGAUGCAGGUGGUGUGUGUGUGUGUGUGUGUGUGUGUGUGUUUCUUUGGCUUGGUCAGCAGUCAGCCAAGAUCUGUGUCCUUGGGUUAUUGGCUCAUGGUUGCAGUUCCUUGGAAGGAGUUUAUUGUAGCAGGUAAAAUUACAUGAGACCUACCAAAGCUUGUGUGUACUGGAGUCCUAUUUCGGACACUGGCCCUUGGGGCAUUGUAUAAAUGAAGGUUCCCUGCUAAGGUUCCCCUCUCCAUUCUACCAAUCUGGGUAAGAAUUGGAGCAGUAUUAAGGCAUGGAUGGGGAGUGGGAGGUGGCGCUUGUCAGCUGCAGUUUGGACCAGCUUGUUGCAACAUUGCGCUUACCAGGUUCCUGAGAAAGGCAUUUUGCUGGCUUUAGGUCGGGCUGAGAUGCGCAUAAGCUUGCACUCUCAGGAGGCAGCUCUCUACUAAGGAGUCAGUCCUACCAAGGGAAGUCCAGCUGUUCACACUGCCUUUCUUCUGGGCCUGUUUGGAUAAGGGUGUGCCAGGUAUUUGAAGACCCUUGCCUCGUGCAGCUAUUUACACUGAUUGCAGUAGGAACUGUAUGCCUUAUUUCUUUUCCCGCCUGCCUGUGAUAUUGUUUCCAGCAUGCUGAGAAAAGUUGAUUUUAUGUUGAAUGAAUUCAGGUAUUUGUUACCAAGUUAGUCCAGAUAAGGGUUUGGCCUUCUUUUGAACUUGCUGUUUCUGUGUAGUUUCUUUGUAGUUCAACAUUCUUGUAAUUGUGAGUGGCCCAGGGCACCUAGUGGUUUAUGCUUUCAAAAGCAGUUCAGAAUAUUUAUUGAAUUUCAUUUCUGCCUUGAGGAUAGCUAGUGCUUACAGCCUGGGAAAGGCUUUUUCAGCCUGUGUGCUUCCACAGAUGGGAGCACCACUACAGAAAGUGGUUUAGAAGCGUUCACCUUGGGGUUUUGGUAUGAGGCACAUUCCAGGGUUUUUAUUUAUUUAUUGAAAAUUUUUAAUUUUUUUUUUAUUGUAGACACAGGGGUCUCACUAUGUUGCCCAGGCUGGUCUUGAACUUCUGUCCUCAAGUGAUCUUCCCACCUUGGCCUCCCAAACUGCUGGGAUUACAGGCAUGAACCAUCACGCCUGACCAUGUUCCAGAUUUGUAACUUGGUCAUUUUGAGUUCCUCUUCACUCUGACUAGGAAAAGACCUGGUUAUUUGACCUGAGGGCACAGAAUUUUGCUUGAGUUUAGGGAAGGCUAUUUCCUCUUCAGAGAAAGAUACCUGCUAAAGUCGCAGGUCCUCGAGAAACUUGCUUUACGUCUCUGAGCCUUGUUUUCCUUUUCAAAAAAUCUCUCAUGCUUUAGAAAUUUCUGAUAAGACUGUAAACUCUCCUGUCCAGAGUAGCUUGAAGUGUCUCUGUCACUUUUUUUUUCCUUGAUGACCUUUUACAUGGAAUUAAAAAUAGGGCAGAACAUAGCUCCAGAGGGGAAAAAAGUUGGUUGGGGACCAGAGCCUAUCAGGUUGCUAAUGCUGUAACCUUAAGGAAUACCCUUUCCUGGGCUGCCUUCCUUUCACCUGGGGAAGGAUUUGGCUUUGGGGAGGUAAGAGCUUGAAACAUGGGAUGAGAGAGGAGUCACUGCUACCUCUGAUUUGCUCAAAGCCAUGGCAGUUGUUUAGAAUUCUCUACCUCUACUGUCACCUAACAGGCAGGCUUCAUCUGCAGGCCUUCCAAAUAGUGGAAGUUCACAGGUAGAAAAUUUAGGUCCCUGAAUCCGUGGGUUCGCUGUCUCAGCCCAUUCAGAACAAUUCUUUAGGUACUGGCCUCACUGGAGAAAGAAGUGAUCCAGAAGAACAGUCUAGUGACCAGGAGAUCUGAGGGUAGGGUGGGAGUGACGCUAGAGCACCAAGGGGGGCUUUACAGCUGUGUUCUCAUGGAGGACAGGCUUCUGCUCAUUCUGGCUUUCCCACUCUUGUGGUUCCCAGUUGCAGUUUUCCAGUUAGUUUUAUUACUUCCUUUUCUUUUGAUCCAUUCCCUAAACUGCCUUGAGUGGAGGCAUUUGUUUAGUGCUUAUCGUGUGCAUAUCCUUGCCUGGCUAGCAUACCCAUGUUUCUGUGUCUCUCUCCGUGUGAGGCAUUGUAUUGAGCUAUUUAUACAGAUUGUUUUAUCCUUACCACAAUGCUGUGGGAUAGGUGGUGUCCCCAUUUUAUAGGUGAGAAAACAGACCUAGAGAAAACAACUUGUUCAGUGACACUUCGUGUAUGUCUUUUCCUGAACCCUGUGCUGAAUUUUCCAAGGAGCCUAGUUACUACAUUGUCUAAAACUAAGAAAGAGCAGACAUAAUGUAGGCCCUUCGGCCCCCUUCCUUUUUGGUUAACUGAGUUAUGCCAAUUUCAGCAGUAUGCUGACUGUACACUUCAUUGUAUUUUAGAGAAAUCUGUUUCGCUGUGAAUGCAUAAAGGCUAAGGAGGGAGGAACAACCCUUGUUUGCUGCUGCAUCUCUUGGGACUUGGGCAAAUUCAACUUUGCACGUGGCAGAUCUCUUGGGAAAGCCACUUGGGUUUUAAAGGGAAAUAUUUUAAAGGUAAUUCCAAGGUUGUUAAGUAAUUUUUGUUCACAUGGUUGAGUUUUCUUCACUGUGGGACUGAGACUGCCGCAGAUUACGUUACUGUCAGUUCCUCACUUUUUCCACUUGGCAAGAAAAAAAAAAAGAUUCGGCCUGGUGUGGUGGCUCACGCCUAUAAUCCUAGCACUUUGGGAGGCCGAUGCGGGCAGAUCACCUGAGGUUGGAGUUGGAGACCAGCUUGGCUAACAUAGUGAAAGCCCGUUUCUACUAAAAAUACAAAAAAUUAGCCGGGCGUGGUGAUGCGUGCCUGUAAUCCCAGCUACUUGGGAGGCUGAGGCAGGAGAAUCGCUUGACCCUGGGAGGUGGAGGUUGCAGUGAGCUGAGAUUGCGCCAUUGCACUCCAGCUUGGGCAACAAGAGCGAAACUCCGUCUCCAAAAAACAAAAACAAAAACAAAAAAACAAUUCCCCACCCAUGCACAAAAUUUUCUGUGUAUCCGUAAAUCAAAUGUAGUCGAUGUUCCAGAUUUGUAAUGAUCACAGUCCUCAUGGAAGAAGGAAAUUCUUAGAGCUCAGUUGGAAGAGAAACAGCAGUCUUUCAGUCUUCAUAGAAGAUAAAGCUCUGGGGAUGACAGCCCCUGGCCUUCUCCCAAAGGAUCUAGUUGCCAGAUGUCUUCAGGGUCACCACGUGAGAUUGGAAGGCAGUCUUGAAAUCUUAAUUUCAUGCGGGAGGAGAGACUACAUGACGGCUACAUCUGUAGUUGGAACAGUAUAUUUAUGGAGCACUGGAAAGCCUUACUGUGUUUAUAGGAUAAAGGAGUCAGGCUACUCUCUGGAGGAAGCAGAACUAUUUACCUCUGAGACUGAAAUGUGAUAUCUUAUAUUUGCACAAAAAAGAUUCGGCCUGGCGCGGUGGCUCACGCCUGUAAUCCUAGCACUUUGGGAGGCCGAUGCGGGUGGAUCACCUGCGGUCAGGAGUUUAGUGUGUUGUGCGAGAGGAAGAAAAAAACAUAUAUACAACUGUCUUACACCAAGGUUGGGAGAGGGCCAGGGCCAAGAGAGGUUUUCUGCUCUUCUGAUACUGACCCGAGCCUCAGACUAUGGCAUGAAACUGCCAAUCCUGCGUUCCAACCCUGAGGACCAGAUCCUGUAUCAAACUGAGCGGUACAAUGAGGAGACCUUUGGCUACGAAGUGCCCAUCAAAGAGGAGGGGGACUACGUGCUGGUCUUGAAAUUUGCAGAGGUCUACUUUGCACAGUCCCAGCAAAAGGUAUUUGAUGUACGAUUGAAUGGCCACGUCGUGGUGAAGGACUUGGAUAUCUUUGAUCGUGUUGGGCAUAGCACAGCUCACGAUGAAAUUAUACCUAUGAGCAUCAGAAAGGGGAAGCUGAGUGUCCAGGGGGAGGUGUCCACCUUCACAGGGAAACUCUACAUUGAGUUUGUCAAGGGGUACUAUGACAAUCCCAAGGUCUGUGCACUCUACAUCAUGGCUGGGACAGUGGAUGAUGUACCAAAGCUUCAGCCUCAUCCGGGAUUGGAGAAGAAAGAAGAGGAAGAAGAAGAAGAAGAAUAUGAUGAAGGGUCUAAUCUCAAAAAACAGACCAAUAAGAACCGGGUGCAGUCAGGCCCCCGCACACCCAACCCCUAUGCCUCGGACAACAGCAGCCUCAUGUUUCCCAUCCUGGUGGCCUUCGGAGUCUUCAUUCCAACCCUCUUCUGCCUCUGCCGGUUGUGAGAACAAAUGACUAUCCUGAACAGGGUGGAGGGGUGUGGGAAAGAAACCAGCCAUAUUGGUUUUGGUUUCUGUAUUUUUCACAAUGAUUAAUGAACAAAAACAAAGAGAAAAAAACACACAUCAAUUAAAGGAGACAAAAAGAGGCAGAGCGAGUAGAGAGCAGCCCUCAUUCACCACCUGGUCCCAGACGUGCUUCAGUCCUCGUCCUCUCUUUGUGGCUGGCUCCCAGCCUUCUCUUUCCUCUUGAGGAUACUUAGGGUAAACUGGAUCCUUCCUGCUCAAGGAUCCUCAUUUGUAUACCUAGUGGAAAGGACUCUGAACUCAGAGGAGUCACUGUUCCUUUUUUUAGGUUAGAAAUUAACAGCAGGGAAAUGCCAUCUUAUUACCUGAGACGACCAGCACUGGGAGUUAGGUACGGUCUGAAGUUAUGUCUAGAUAAGACUUCAGACGUCCUGGGAUUGAAAGAAUGUGUGUGAAGGGGUAGAAUUUGUGCGGUAAAGACUUAAAAAAAAAAGUAGGGAGAUUAAAAAAAAAGAAAGAAAAUGCUUCCUUAUCUGGAAGCCUUUCUGGAUUAAUCCAGUGAUGGUCCCACCUUUAGUGUUUGAGCUUUGUCAUUGCUUGUCUCCCUGGCAUGUGCCAGUUAUAGACUGUCCAGCAUCCAAGACGUUUCGGUUAUGUCGGGUCCUCAGAUCGCCUCUGACUUGUUACCACAACAAAUCAUUUUGAUUUCAGUGCCUGUUGGGGACUUGAUUUCUUCUCAGUUUUGUUUGUUUGUUUGUUUCCUUAAUCUGGCUCAUUUGAAAUUUCUUCUCCCUCUCAACCAUCCCACUAAGUUAUAGCCAAGAAGGGAAGGAGACACGGGGAUUUGGGGUUCUCUGCUUGAAUGUCUUCUCCUUUACCACCUCACCUUGUUGGUACCUCCCUCCCUGGAUCUCUGAGCCAGCAGCCAGGAGGACCUGACCCAGCAGUUCUUUACUGGCCCCUUUGUAGGGCCUUGCUGCCAGGGGGCAGGGAUGCUUUCCAGCCUGCAGCAACAGAACACUUGACCUUAAAAGUCUCUUCUGGUCUUUGGAUUAGAAAAGGCUUAUGUUAGCAUAGCUUAAGAGCAACCUCAGAGAUUUGAGCCCUACUAAGUGACUGACCACUGUUUAGAGUGUCUGGUAUCUGAUGUUCAUUUAUUCCCAUGUUCUUGUGUGUCACAGUUCAGCCAGUUUUGGUUUAUGCCUAGAGCUACUUCAAGGAACUAGACUAAUUAGCUAUAUAGGCCCAGCGAUGCUUCUUAUUGAUCUUAAUAGUAUGCCCCUCCUUCCCCUGUCCUUUCAUUUCUCUAUCCAAGUAGCAGUCAGGUUCUUGGUGUGAUGGGACUGAAAGAAUUCCAGUCAGCCAGAGCCUUGGCAGCUCUGAAGCUAACCUUAGCAUCUAAGUGUCGAUCUUGAAUUCCCUGAAAAAAUUUCUAUAGGAAAUGAAGCUUCCCUGGUCCCCUCCUUUCUGGCCAUUGUCAUCCAUUUCCCAGUUAGGGCAACAAUGAAGGAGGACCCAGCCAAGCUAGAAGGAAUUUUGUGGAUGGGAGACAGCAGGAUUAGCUUCAGCUUGGGCUGGAGCAGUCAAUAUAGGAUCUCAGGCCAGGCCCGCUUUUCUAGAAUGUGUUUAAUUUUGAGUUUGCUUUAUUAGAUAUGUUUUUUAAGAGCUCUGUAUAUUUGAACUGCUCCUUAUGUGACAAAAUAGGUAGCUCUUGGGCUCAUGUCCUGGGUUUUGGCUCUUUAAUGAUUACUCCAGGCCAGCAUUUAGUCGUUUGAGAAUUGUAGCCUGUUGUUUUCGCUGUGACUUGGGUCUCAGUGCUAGGGUAUUGAGUCAGGCAGCUGGAGGGUUGUGGCCCGAGGCUGCAGUCAGAGGUAUACUUCCCAUAGUGCUUCACACAGCUCCCCUGCUUCUAAAGGAUAAGGUACUGUAGCCUUGGUCCUGGGGACCACCUGCCUGGGGCAGUGGACAUCCUAACUAAACAGGCUUCUGGCAGUAGCUUUGGUUCCUAUCCCAUCGAAAUUCCCCAAAGCCCUGGGCCACUGCCAUUGGGUUAGUCAAGAUGAAGGAGGAGGACUGGCUGCCUCCAUUUUGCCUUGUUUGUUAGUUUGCCUGGGUCUGUCUGAGGAAGGAGGGGGUCCCGCCUUCCACCUCAACACAUCCCUUCAGUGACUCAGAGUCUCAGAAGGAAACCCUGACUCCUGGGGCCAUUUCCUAAUGGUACUGUAAGCCAAGCAGCUUUGCUUCUGCCUCUGUUUCCAAGCCCACCCUUUUCCCCUGAGCUCAGGGUUAGGGAUGGGCGCUUUCCUCUCUGGUUGUGAACGAAAGGAAGGAACAUCUUUCUAUGGCUAACAAAAACUAAAGGGGAAGUGAGGAAACAGGAAGAAGUAUGGUGGGGGCUGGGGUAGACUCCCCUGGAGCCAAGCCUAUCCAGCUAACAAGAGCUCCCUGGGGCUGGUCACAGCUGGCUCAUGAUGCUGAACUUGAAAGUUUUUUUGUUUUUGUUUUUGUUUUGUGGCUCCUCCAAGAUAUAGGUACAUGAAGUUUAGGUUAAAGGGGUGGGAUUCUUUAUUUUUAUUUUUGUAUUGUAUGUGUCAAGAAUUACUCUGUUGUUCACCUUUUGCUUUUUGCACUGUUUGUUCUCUUAUCUGUAUUUUGAGCUUAGUGCUAGGACUGAGAGGCUGCACCAUAGGGAAUGUAUGGGAGAUGGUGAGGGGUGCCAGUGAGGGGUGCGUGGAGGAGAGGCCUGGGCUCCUCUACUGGAUCUACACUCUGUCCCAGGUUUUUAGAUCCCACUGAGCCCAGCUGACUGAAAACAAGGACAGUCAGGGUGAAACUUCUUUUGCCAGAAGUGUGGCCUGAGUUGAAUUUCUGGGAGGAUGACGCAGAUGUCUGCUGCAGAGCUGGGCUGAGAGUUCUGCAGUCUAGCUCUGACUUAGGUCAGGGGCCUGUUGGUCUCUCAUUGGACGUUUUUGGGUCUCACUCAUGCUUACUGAAACAUUGUGCCAAGAAACUCUGUGGGAUUUGUGUCCCUUAAACCAGACUCACUUUUCUGAAAAAUCUCCAUUGUUGAGGAGAGGCUGCUCAAUCGACACCCCGAGUUCUCAUGACUGGGAAGAUAGUUUUCUUCAGGUGUCAAUGGCGUUAGACUCCCAGGAAGACUAGCCCUGCCCACAGGGCCACCUGUUGGUUUGAGAGCGUGUUCGUGUUCUCUUGCCCUCCCUGCCUAAGAGCUACUGGGAUCACGUUAGCGGGCAUUUAGGCUUUGAUGAGAGGGCACAGUUUGAGUUAGGUUUACCUCCCCCUUUCUGUGCCUGGGAACUGUUUGGUCCAGCUUUAGAACUGUGGUUUUGACUUCCUUAUCUCUUGGGAGAAGCUUCUGUUUUAAGGAAUUUCUCUUCCUUCUUCUCCUGCCUCUAGCCUCUCCUGGAAAGGCCUGGAUAUGGUUUCUAAAAUCUCAGCUGAGAACUUCAGAAAACAGCAGCAGUAUUUUCCUUUUCCUAGUGCUAAAAUCCCUUUCCCUAGAAAUUGGCUCACCUUGGGAAACCCAGGGAAAGAAUCAGCAGGUUCUCUGCCCUCCCUAGGGGUUGGGGAAGGACCCACCCCGGUCAGCACAGUGCCUUUUCCUCUCCUGCUCUGAGCCAGGGUGGGGCAUUCCCUCUAGAUUCAGGUUUGGGCAGGGGUCCUAUAGUCCCUGCCAUGGGGCUGCUUCCCUGUCCCUUCCCUCCCCUUUGCUGGCCUACUCUGGCAUAAUUCAAGUGUCUUCUUGCCUUGGGGAUCCUUAGUGGCAUCAAAUGGCAACAUGGAAUAUUGUCCUCCAUGCCCCUCCAGAAGGACCUAGGAGAGUAGGUGAGCUUUCCAAAGUGAGAGACGAAUCUUUCUUUCUUUUUUUUUUUAAAGGGCAGGAUGGGUAUGCUUUGGGCUUUCUCCUUCUGUGGCCCCGGAGGAAGGAGAGACUGAGGCAAGGCAAAGUGAUAGUACACGGAAGCAGAACCGGAAACACCCAGGAACUGUUCAGAAAUCUCAGAAGAAAUCUGCUUCUCUUCGAUGGAAAGAUAUAAUUAACGAUCAAAGAGCUCUAAGAAAAUUGCAAAGAAGCCUUAAUGUUCAAGCUUUAGAAAGAUCAGAGCAAUUUUUCUCUUUCAGUCCAAACUAAGACUCUCUGUAUUUAAAUCUCUCUGGGGCAAGAGGGCUAGAUUUCCUCAUUUUGUUAUGAGACUAGAUUGGUACCAGUAGAUCAGCUGCCUAGCGAGGGCAGGUUUCUUCUUUGCAUCUGUGUGGCUUGCUUCCAGUCUGGCCUGUCCUUUCCAGCUGCCUUUUGUCUAGCCUGCUAUGGGGGGCCAGAUUAUCUUGAUAAGAGCAGGUGAUUUGGGGACUAGCUGGGUUGGCAGGAAAAGAGCAGGAUGGAUCUCUUGGGACAGGUUCCCCCAGGAGUAUAAACACAAGGAGCCAGGAUUGUGCUGGCAGCCAAGGAAACAGUAGUGCCUGUUUGAGUUGGCAGAGAGGGCCUUGGCACCUCUUGCAUCCAGGCAGUCUUGUGAGAUGGGGGCACAUAGCACUGGGGAAAGCAGAACUCCAUUCUCACCUCUAUUUUGAGCUUCAGUGCUUUAUUUCAGUAUGAGGAAAAACAACAACAAACUGAAGUGCGCUUUCCGUCCUUUCAAAGGACAACUGUCGGGAAGGGAGAGCCGAGUUGCGAGGUAGGAGGGGAGCACUGGCAGGGAGAGACAUUCUUGACUCCUCUCUUCCCUGGUGUGUUGUGAUCCAGGGAAUGAAAAGAAAUUUGACCCUGGAUUGGUUCUCUCCUUGGACUUAAGGAAUCUUACCUUUUCCUUCCACAAAGUUCUCCCAGGCAAGGACCAGCUGCCCAUUCUGAGCCCAGGGCAGCCUCUUCAACCAUUAUUGGUCUAACCUGGCUUGUCAGGAAACCAAGCCCACCCUUCCACAUUGGGCCUGGCUGCUCUAUUCUGUACCAAGUACUGGAGAAAAAGCAUCAAGUUCUUAGCCCUUGUAGCUUCUACCCUAGUUUCCCAUCCUCUCUCUGUGGAGGCCAAACCAACUCUUUGCCAGCAGCCACAACAUGCAUUGACAGCGGCACAGUGAGAUAUAACUGAUGGGCUUUGAACCUGGUUGGCCGGGGAAGCUGUAGGGGUGGAUAGAGCUGGCUUUCCUUCUGGGCUGUCUCCAUCUGACCCUACCCCUUCCAUGUCCCACCCCACUCCCACCAAAAAGUACAAAAUCAGGAUGUUUUUCACUGUCCAUUGCUUUGUGUUUUAAUAAACAAUUUGCAGUGACA